GCCACGGGCCUCCCCGCACCAGCAGAAGUCGGAGUCGCUGUUGGGGGCGGUGUCUAUGGUUGAGCUGAGGGCGCAGGCGCCACGGCCCGUCGAGCUGGGUUCCAAGGCGGCUGGCGGCGGUAGCGUCUCUGUUUCCUUGUGGGCGCUCGCGCGGCCCUGGUCUGUAGAGAAUGCCAAAUGAGGGAAUCCCCCACUCAAGUCAAACUCAGGAGCAAGACUGUUUACAGAGUCAACCUGUCAGUAAUAAUGAAGAAAUGGCAAUCAAGCAAGAAAGUGGUGGUGAUGGGGAGGUGGAGGAGUACCUCUCCUUUCGUUCUGUGGGUGACGGGCUGUCCACCUCUGCUGUGGGGUGCGCAUCAGCAGCUCCGAGGAGAGGGCCAGCCCUGCUGCACAUCGACCGACAUCAGAUCCAGGCAGUAGAGCCUAGCGCCCAGGCCCUUGAGCUGCAGGGUUUGGGUGUGGACGUCUAUGACCAGGACGUGCUGGAACAGGGAGUGCUUCAGCAGGUGGACAAUGCCAUCCAUGAGGCCAGCCGUGCCUCCCAGCUCGUUGACGUGGAGAAGGAGUAUCGGUCGGUCCUGGAUGACCUCACGUCAUGUACGACAUCCCUAAGGCAAAUCAAUAAAAUUAUUGAACAGCUUAGCCCUCAAGCUGCCACCAGCAGAGACAUCAACAGGAAACUAGAUUCUGUAAAACGACAGAAGUAUAAUAAGGAACAACAGCUAAAAAAGAUCACUGCAAAACAAAAGCAUCUCCAGGCCAUCCUUGGAGGAGCAGAGGUGAAAAUUGAACUAGAUCACGCCAGUCUGGAGGAGGAUGCAGAGCCGGGGCCAUCCAGUCUUGGCAGCAUGCUCAUGCCUGUCCAGGAGACUGCCUGGGAAGAGCUCAUCCGCACUGGCCAGAUGACACCUUUUGGUACCCAGAUCCCUCAGAAACAGGAGAAAAAGCCCAGAAAAAUCAUGCUUAAUGAAGCAUCAGGCUUCGAAAAGUAUUUGGCAGAUCAAGCAAAACUGUCUUUUGAAAGGAAGAAGCAAGGUUGUAAUAAAAGAGCAGCUAGAAAAGCUCCAGCCCCAGUCACGCCUCCAGCCCCAGUGCAAAAUAAAAACAAACCAAACAAGAAAGCCAGAGUUCUGUCCAAAAAAGAGGAGCGUUUGAAAAAGCACAUCAAGAAACUCCAGAAGAGGGCUUUGCAGUUCCAGGGGAAAGUGGGAUUGCCAAAGGCAAGGAGACCUUGGGAGUCAGACAUGAGGCCAGAGGCAGAGGGAGACUCUGAGGGUGAAGAGUCUGAGUAUUUCCCCACAGAGGAGGAGGAAGAGGAGGAAGAUGACGAGGUGGAGGGGGCAGAGGCGGACCUGUCUGGAGAUGGUACUGACUAUGAGCUGAAGCCUCUGCCCAAGGGCGGGAAACGGCAGAAGAAAGUGCCAGUGCAGGAGAUUGAUGAUGACUUUUUCCCAAGUUCUGGGGAAGAAGCUGAAGCUGCUUCUGUAGGAGAAGGAGGAGGAGGAGGUCGGAAAGUGGGAAGAUACCGAGAUGAUGGAGAUGAAGAUUAUUAUAAGCAGCGGUUAAGGAGAUGGAAUAAACUGAGACUGCAGGACAAAGAGAAACGUCUGAAGCUGGAGGACGAUUCUGAGGAAAGUGAUGCUGAAUUUGACGAAGGUUUUAAAGUGCCAGGUUUUCUGUUCAAAAAGCUUUUUAAGUACCAGCAGACAGGUGUUAGGUGGCUGUGGGAAUUGCACUGCCAGCAGGCAGGAGGAAUUCUGGGAGAUGAAAUGGGAUUGGGCAAGACCAUCCAGAUAAUUGCCUUCUUGGCAGGUCUGAGCUACAGCAAGAUCAGGACUCGUGGUUCAAAUUACAGGUUUGAGGGGUUGGGUCCAACUGUAAUUGUCUGUCCAACAACAGUGAUGCAUCAGUGGGUGAAGGAAUUUCACACGUGGUGGCCUCCGUUCAGAGUGGCAAUUCUACAUGAAACCGGUUCCUAUACCCACAAAAAGGAGAAACUAAUUCGAGAUGUUGCUCAUUGUCAUGGAAUUUUGAUCACAUCUUACUCCUACAUUCGAUUGAUGCAGGAUGACAUUAGCAGGUAUGACUGGCACUAUGUGAUCUUGGACGAAGGACACAAAAUUCGAAAUCCAAAUGCUGCUGUCACCCUUGCUUGCAAACAGUUUCGCACCCCUCAUCGGAUCAUUCUGUCUGGCUCACCGAUGCAAAAUAACCUCCGAGAGCUGUGGUCGCUCUUUGACUUCAUCUUCCCGGGAAAGUUAGGCACGUUGCCUGUGUUUAUGGAGCAGUUCUCCGUCCCCAUCACCAUGGGGGGAUAUUCAAAUGCUUCCCCAGUACAGGUCAAAACUGCUUACAAGUGUGCAUGUGUCUUACGAGAUACCAUAAAUCCAUACCUACUGCGGAGAAUGAAGUCAGAUGUCAAGAUGAGCCUUUCUUUGCCAGAUAAAAAUGAACAGGUCUUAUUUUGCCGUCUUACAGAUGAGCAGCAUAAAGUCUACCAAAAUUUCGUUGAUUCCAAAGAAGUUUACAGGAUUCUCAAUGGAGAGAUGCAGAUUUUCUCCGGACUUAUAGCCCUAAGAAAAAUUUGCAACCACCCUGAUCUCUUUUCUGGAGGUCCCAAGAAUCUCAAAGGUCUUCCUGAUGAUGAACUAGAAGAAGAUCAGUUUGGGUACUGGAAACGUUCUGGGAAAAUGAUUGUUGUUGAGUCUUUGUUGAAAAUAUGGCACAAGCAGGGUCAGCGAGUAUUGCUGUUUUCUCAGUCAAGGCAGAUGCUGGACAUACUUGAAGUAUUCCUUAGAGCCCAAAAGUAUACCUAUCUCAAGAUGGAUGGUACCACUACAAUAGCUUCAAGACAGCCACUGAUUACGAGAUACAAUGAGGACACAUCCAUAUUUGUGUUUCUUCUGACCACGCGGGUGGGCGGCUUAGGUGUCAACCUGACGGGGGCAAACAGAGUUGUCAUCUAUGACCCAGACUGGAACCCAAGCACGGACACGCAGGCCCGGGAGCGAGCAUGGAGAAUAGGCCAGAAGAAGCAAGUGACUGUGUACAGGCUCCUGACUGCGGGCACCAUUGAAGAAAAGAUCUACCACCGACAAAUCUUCAAGCAGUUUUUGACAAAUAGAGUGCUAAAAGACCCAAAACAAAGGCGGUUUUUCAAAUCCAAUGAUCUCUAUGAGCUAUUUACUCUGACUAGUCCUGAUGCAUCCCAGAGCACUGAAACAAGUGCAAUUUUUGCAGGAACUGGAUCAGAUGUUCAGACACCCAAAUGCCAUCUAAAAAGAAGGAUUCAACCAGCCUUUGGAGCAGACCAUGAUGUUCCAAAACGCAAGAAGUUCCCUGCUUCUAACAUAUCUGUAAAUGAUGCCACAUCAUCUGAAGAGAAAUCUGAGGCUAAAGGAGCUGAAGUAAAUGCAGUAACUUCUAAUCGAAGUGAUCCUUUGAAAGAUGACCCUCACAUGAGUAGUAAUGUAACUAGCAAUGAUAGGCUUGGAGAAGAGACAAAUGCAGUAUCUGGACCAGAAGAGUUGUCAGUGAUUAGUGGAAAUGGGGAAUGUUCAAAUUCUUCAGGAACAGGCAAAACUUCUAUGCCAUCUGGUGAUGAAAGCAUUGAUGAAAAGUUAGGUCUUUCUUACAAAAGAGAAAGACCCAGCCAGGCUCAAACAGAAGCUUUUUGGGAGAAUAAACAAAUGGAAAAUAAUUUUUAUAAGCACAAGUCAAAAACAAAACAUCAUAGUGUGGCAGAAGAAGAGACCCUGGAGAAACAUCUGAGACCAAAGCAAAAGCCUAAGAACUCUAAGCAUUGCAGAGACGCCAAGUUUGAAGGAACUCGAAUUCCACACCUGGUGAAGAAAAGGCGUUACCAGAAGCAAGACAGUGAAAACAAGAGUGAGGCCAAGGAACAGAGCAAUGACGAUUAUGUUUUGGAAAAGCUUUUCAAAAAAUCAGUUGGCGUGCACAGUGUCAUGAAGCACGAUGCCAUCAUGGAUGGAGCCAGCCCAGAUUAUGUACUGGUGGAGGCAGAAGCCAACCGAGUGGCCCAGGAUGCCCUGAAAGCACUGAGGCUCUCUCGUCAGCGGUGUCUGGGAGCAGUGUCUGGUGUUCCCACCUGGACUGGCCACAGGGGGAUUUCUGGUGCACCAGCAGGAAAAAAGAGUAGAUUUGGUAAGAAAAGGAAUUCUAACUUCUCUGUGCAGCAUCCUUCAUCAACAUCUCCAACAGAGAAGUGCCAGGAUGGCAUCAUGAAAAAGGAGGGAAAAGAUAAUGUCCCUGAGCAUUUUAGUGGAAGAGCAGAAGAUGCAGACUCUUCAUCCGGGCCCCUCGCUUCCUCCUCACUCUUGGCUAAAAUGAGAGCUAGAAACCACCUGAUUCUGCCAGAGCGUUUAGAAAGUGAAAGCGGGCACCUGCAGGAAGCUUCUGCCCUGCUGCCCACCACAGAACACGAUGACCUUCUGGUGGAGAUGAGAAACUUCAUCGCUUUCCAGGCCCACACUGAUGGCCAGGCCAGCACCAGGGAGAUACUGCAGGAGUUUGAAUCCAAGUUAUCUGCAUCACAGUCUUGUGUCUUCCGAGAACUAUUGAGAAAUCUGUGCACUUUCCAUAGAACUUCUGGUGGUGAAGGAAUUUGGAAACUCAAGCCAGAAUACUGCUAAACAACAUUGCUUCCUAAACUUUCAAGUCCCUUUUUCUAACGGGCAUUUCUGAUUAUUAAUUUAUUAUUAAUAAUCAUGUUUGUCAAUGGAAGUUGGCUGCACUUGAUGUUUGUUUGCAUGAUGUCUACCUCAGAAUUAAAACUUUAAGGAAGAAGAAACUCUUCUCUGAAAGUUAAAAGUUUUAAUAAUGCUAGCUAAAGGAGAAAAUACUUGGAUUGAUUUUUUUUUUUUUGGCAAUCUAAUUAUAUUGUAAAUCAGGUACCUAACAGUUACUCCUUGGAGCACAUUUGUUCCUUUACCCAAAAGAUGCUGUCAGGGAGCACAGUUAGAAGUUUGCAGAACAGAAAUCUCAAUAUUUUUUUUUAUUGGUGCUAAAAACAGGUCUUACAUUCAGUCAGACCUGUUCAAUAAGUUCAUCAAUAUCUGAUAACAGCAUUAUUUUGAUGCUUAAACUUUAAACAUUUAUAUUUACCAUUUGCCACCCACAAAGGUCAGGUUUGUUAUUUGUUGUUUGAUAAUUAUAUUAAUUUUCUUGGAAAGAUCCUCUUUUCAAGGUACUGGUAAAUUGGUGAGUAUUUUUAUUAGUAAAGCAUGAAAUAGUAUGGUAAUAAAUGAUAAGACAUGUAUUUGUGGAAAGCUGUAGGGUAUUCAGUUUACCCUGGCUUUCCUUUAAGCAGAGGGCAUCUUUUUCUCUCCUACAGUCACAAAAUGUGUUAUCAUUAAAAAAAAUCAAAUUAAAGCCAAAAGUAGGUACAUAAAAACCACACACAUGCAUGCACACAAACAUCACUGCAGCCCACAGCAGACCCAGCCGUUGUUACCAUGAAGUGACACCACUCCAGGCCUCUCUUGUCUGCAGGCUGGCAGGCUGUCUUCUCUCCAGUUGCCUUCGUCUUGCGCCUGCCUUUGCAUUCCUUGCGACGGGCUUUCUUGUUUCUGCGGUUUGGAUUCCAGCCAAGGCUGUUUGUAUCUCACUACUGUUUAUGUGUUUGUGGUUCUGUGAUGGUGUUGCUUUGAUCCUCAGUUUAUUUUCUUACCCAUGUUUUUCUUGUUUCCUUCUCAGGAUGAUUUUAUCAUCUCAUCUUUGAAGUGUUGUUUUCCGAAAUUCAUCGUAUUCCUGAAAUUUCUUCUUAGCUGUCUUAGUGCAGUUUGUUUCUUGGAUUUGUAUUCUCUGGCAUGCUCUUUUCCUCUCUCUCAUUUUUCUGUAGUAUGCCUGCCCUCCUACCCUGCUAUUUCUUUACAUCUCUCUCAUGCUUAACAUGGAUAGCUGUGUCCAGAUCUUCUGUCUGCUCAUCCAUGUGACUCAGAGAGGAGGGUUCUGGGCAGGGGGGCCUUGCCGGACUGCAUGAGAGGACAUGAGUUUUGCUUUCUCUGCUCUAAUAUUUUGCUUAAGCCAAGAAUCCUUUUCUUAGAGAUGUUCUAUAUGAUUCCUGUCAGGAUUUUCUAGUUUUUUUUGGAUUAUAGCUUGUUCAUUUCUUUUGUUUUUAGUUUGGUUUAUAUAUAAUGAGGGAAGAAGAUGAUUACAUUAUUUUUGUCACUUUGCCAUCAUUGUUUAGAAGUCAUAGAAAGAAUUUUUAAAUAGGCCAAUAAGUCUUAAACUUGAGUACUUGGCUUAGAAGAAAGUCAAAACUCCUUCCUUUUUGACUAAGUGGUUUGUUUCUGGGGAGCUCUUAAUUUCUAUUUUUAUAAUCAUUAGCCUAUAAGGAAAUUGUGUCUUCCUUGUUCUCAGGGUGAUCUGCUGACCUUGUUCACUCAUGAAGCAUUUGGGUAUCAUACUUAUAGUGUCUGAAACAUAAACUGUAUUGAGCUAGACAAGGUAUAGCCUCCUCUUCAAGUAGCAAAUACUAUCAAAAGCUAUAAUGCAGUAGGAGCAAGGUGGUCCUUGUUCCAGUUUUUGUCUCAGUUCUGCUGCUGAUGUACCAUGAUCUUGGGAAGGUGGUGUCUCAGUGUGGAGAUCUGACACAUUGUUACCGUGCCUCCUGGCUGGAGGGACUUGGAGAACAAUGCAGUUAAGUAGAAUGGUUUUAACAAUACAGAGAAAUUUAUUCAUUUAGAUAAAAAUCUGAUUUUUAGAACUUUAAAAGCUUUGUACAGUGUAAAUAGAUUUAAUGUAUUUAACAUGCUUUAUCAGCACAAAUAAAGGAUUUUAAAAUUUUGUCAAAAAAUUAAAUGUUAAUACUAUCACCAUUAAAAAUGUUCAAGCAAUAGUCUGCCUCCCCACCCCCACACCAUCUUGCACCUGUUCCACAGCUAAGUACAGCCCUAGGUUUGGUGUGUAUUCUCCAUGCAUUUAGAGAAUCACAUGACACAGACUGCUGCUAUAAUGUCAUUUUCCCAUUCUUCCUUUACUAAUAAAAUUUUUGAGUUUUACCUGGACGUCUGGCUGCUCAGCUUAAGACUACUUCUCAGCCUCUCUUAUAGUUAAUUGUGGCCAUAUGACUAAGUUUUAAACUUCCCAAUUGGCCCUUUAAAGAAGCAGGGUAUGCACUCUCCUUGACAUUCCCCUUUCUUGCUGGCUGGGAGGCCAAUGGGAGCUUCAGUAGUGACCUGGCAUCUCAAGAGAUGGAAGUGAUGUGUUGAGGAAGGAGAAGUUGGCCUGCCAGUCUUGAACUGCUCUCCUUUGACCUGUUAUUUAAGAGUAAAAUAAAAUACUGACUUGCUUAAGCUACUGUCUUUUGAAGUCUAUUAUAGCAAUUAGUUUGCUUUAAAUAUGUAAUUUAUAUUAAUGGCCUUAUACCAUCCUUAUUUUGCAACUAACUUUUCAUUUAAUAUUAUAUGCAAGACAUUUCUAUUCCUGUAAGUAUAGCUCUGCCUGCACAGAAUUGUUGGAUUAAUGAUGUAGAUUUUAAAUGUCAGUGGAUGUAGCAGAAUUGCUUGCAUCAAUUCACCCUCCAUAAAAGGACCCAUUUCUCCAAACCCUUGCCAACAGUAAGUGGUAUCAAUAUCGAUAGGUUGUUUUGUUUUGUUUUAACCAGUCUCGUGAUUGAAAGUACCUUGUUUUCACUUGAAUUUCCCUGAUUACGUACAAAAUCAAACAUUUCCAUGUUUAUUGGCCAUUUGUAGAUCUCUACCGUACAUUGCCUAUUAGUGUUAUGUUGGCCUAGUUUUCCUGUGGGUUGUUUAUCUUUUAGGAUUGCUCCCCUAAACAAAAACAAAAAGGCAGUUAUUCCAAUGAUCAACAAAUAUUCUUUUCUCCACCAGUUUAAAAUGUCAGCUUUCAACUCAUCACAUGCUAAGUUGUCUAUUUCUGUCCUGUGGAUCCAGGUGUUGGUUCUACCAACCACACUCCUCACGCUGUCAUUUGGUGCUUUGCAUUGUGUUUUGCCAUUCAUGGGCAAGUUCCUUUUCCUUUCUCCCCCUCUUCAGUGUCUUAUACUUGGGUGUUUUCUGUUCCAGCUGAAUCAAGAAUUAGUUUAUUAAAUUCCAGUAAAAUUGUGGUGUUCUUUUGACUAGGAUUGCAUUUGUUUACACAUUAAUUUGAGAAUAAUAGACCUCUUUAUAAUUAAUAUAAUGUUUCUGAUUAGUGUUAUGAUAGGCCUCAUUUUAUUAAAGUCUUUUAUAUUCUUGGAUGAAAUUUUAAUAACUUUCUUCAUAAAUGUCUUGCACAUUUCAUAAUAGGCUUAUUCCUAGGUGUUUUAUAGAUUUUUAGUUUUGGUUGUGAGUCUUUUAACUUACAUAAAAAUAUGGAGAAUUAGCAUAUUCACAUAUCUAUUUUGUGAUGUUUAUCAUACGGAAGUUUUAAAAUAUAGUAAAUUCAGUCUUUCCAUUUUUUUUUGUUUAUUUAAGAACCAUUCCCUAGCUAGGGUCAUGAAUACAUUCUUAUGAAUUAUUAAUCCCAUAUGGAUAGCUAGUUUCCCUAGCACCUUUAAAAAAUAGUUUAUUAUUUUCCUCCUGAUGUAUAAGGCCACCUUUACCAAUUUACAUAUAAUGUACGGAAAUGUUUCUUGGCUCUGCAUUCUGUUAAAUUGGUCCAUUUAUCUAACUUUGCUUAGUAACCCACUGUUUUUAUCAUUGUGGUAUCAUAAUUGAUUAUCACAAAUGGUAGAAUGAUUGUCCUCAAAGUCUUUUCUGGUAUAUAUUGAUAUAAUUGUAUAGCUUUUCUUGGUGUAGUAAAGUACACAGUUAAAUUUUCUAACAUUGAAAUAUCUUUUAGAUUUUCACUUCCAGAAUGGCAAUGUGAAGGGCCCUGUGGACCCACUGUCCUAGGAAUUAGCUAUAACUAGUGAAAAUUGUAACAAAAAAUAAACACCUUCCUCUCAUACAGAGAGACACAAACACUUAAUGCCACUGGAAAUUGUCCUAAAAGCAUGUAGAAUAAAGUAACGCUUAUUCAAGAAAAUCCAAAUCUUGGUAAGAACAGUGAGUCAGACAUUUCAGCCACAACACACUCACUCCCUCCCUCCCAUUUCAGUGGGUGCAGCCAAGAAAACAGAGCUCCGUCUCCCUCAGCUCCCUGUCCAGAGGUAUGGUACCUCACAGGGAGGGGCAAGAUGCCAGCAUUUCUUAUCCCCUCCAGCUUCAAGUGGCAAGAGCUAAAUUCAUGAAGUUAAAAACUAUAAUAAGGAAAAAAUGCACUAAAGGGGUUCAAUAGUAGAUUUGAACUGGCAGAAGAAAUUGUCAGCCAACUGGCAGAUAGAAUAAGAGAGAUAUGCUUUCCAAAGAACAGAGAGAAAAAAAAUGAAAAAUGAGCAAAACCUCAGAGAAAUGUGAAGCACCAUUAUGUGCACCAUUAAGUAUGCAUGUAAUGGGAGUACAAGAAGAGCAGAAGAAAAAGGAAAUAUUUAAAGAUACAAUGACUGAAAACUCUCCAAAUUGAUUGAAAAACAUCUAGGAAGCUUAGUGAACUUCCAGCAUGAUAAAUGCAGAGGGAUUCACAGACACAUCAUAGUCAAAAAUGCUGAAAUCAAAGAUGAGAAAACCUUGAAAGUAGUGAGUGAAAAAAAGAUACAUCACUUAGAGAACAAAAUUAAUACUUGACUUCUCAAAAGAAAUAAUGGAGGCCAGAAGGCAGGUAUAACAGUCAAAGUGCUUGAAGAAAAAAAAACUGUCAACCAAGAAUCCUAUAUCCAGCAAAUGUAUUAUUCAAAAAUAUAAGUGAAAUACUUUCCCAGAUAAACAAAAACAGAAAAAUUGUUGUUAACCAACCUGCCUAAUAAGAAGUAUUAAAUGAAGUUCUUUAGGCUGAAAGCAAGAGAAGAGCACCAGUAAAAGCAAUUAUAUAAUUAUAAAAGUCACAUAAAUGCAUAUUUUUCUCCUCUUAACUGAUUAAAAUGCAACUGUAUCAAAUAAUACGUAUAUGAUGUAUUGGUCUAUAACAUACAGAAAUGUCAUAUAUGUAACAUUUGUCAAAACAGCACAAAGGAGGUGGCUGGGAGCAAAGCUGUAGUAGACUAAUUAAAUGAUGGCAGAUGGUAAAGUAAUAAUUAUAACAAUGUGUUGGAUUUGUAACAUUAAUAGAUACCAUAUGUAUACCUAAAAUAUCACAAAAAGGGGGAAAGGGAAUAUAGCUAUAUAAGAGUAAAGCUUCUAUAUAUUAUUGGAGUUAAGCUUGUGUAAUUCUAACAGAUUCUGAUAAGAUGUAUAUGGUAAACACUAGAGCAACCACUAAUAAAAUAACUCCAGAAAUAUAGUUGAAAAAUCAUUAAUCAAAUUAAAAUACUACCUUAGAAAAUACUCGAUGCAAAAGGCAAUAUUAAAAGAGAAUGAAAAGAACACAAUGGAUACUAGAAAACAAAAAGUAAUGUGUAUUCAACUUAUCAAUAAUAAAUGUUAAUGAAUUUAAUCAGGCAGAGACUAUCAGAUUGGAUUAAAAAUACAUUCCAACUCUAUGUUAUCUAUGCUCCCAUAGAUAACACACUUUAGGCUCAAAGACACAGAUAGAUUAAAAGGAUACAAAAAGAAAUAGUGCAAACAAUUGCCAUAAGAAAGCUGGACUGGCUAUACUAGUGUCAGACAAAGUAGACUUUAAGACAAAAAUGCUCCUAGAGAUAGAGACAUUUUAUAAUGAUAAAAAGGUUAACCCAUCAAAAAGAUAUAACAGUUGUAAACAUAUGUAUGAACUUAACAGUAUCAAAACACAGAAAGCAAAAACUGACAGAAAUGGAAGAAGAAAAUGGUCACAAUAAUAAUUGGAGACUCCAUAACCUAUUUUCAGUAAUGGACAAAACUAGACACAAGGUUAACAAUGAAAUAGAAAACUUGACCAACGCUGUAAACCAACUAGCCCUAACAGACAUCUAUAGAACACUUCACCCAAGCGCUACAGCAUAUACAUUAUCAAAUGCUCAUAGAACAUUCUUCAGGAUAGGCCUUAUGCUAGACCAUGAAACUUCAAUACGUUUAAAAGGAUAGAAAUAAUGCAAAGUGCAUUUUGUGAACAUAAUCACAGGAUUAAAUUAGAAAUAAAAAAUGGGAACAUUUGAAGAACUCACAAUUAGGAAAUUGAACAACACACUACUAAAUGACCAAUAGACCAAAGAAGAAAACAAGAAGGUAAUCAGCACUUUGAGGCUAAUGAAAAUUAAGACACAAGUAAACUGUACGGAUGCAGCUAAAAAAGUGCUUAGAGGAAAUUUAUAGGUGUAAAUGCCUGUAUUAAGGAAGAAAUAAAGCAAUAACCUUUCUUCCACCUUAAGUCACUGAAGAAAGAAGAACAAACUAAACCUAAAGCAAGCAGAAGGAAGGAAAUAAUAAAAUUAGAGUAGAAAUUAAUGAAAGAAUAGAAAAACAAUAGAGAAAAUAUUACUAGAAACUGGUAAUUUGAAAAGAUCAAUAAAUAUGACAAAUAUUUCACUAGGUUGACCAAUAAAAAGGCAAUACUCAAAUUACUAGGAUCUGAUAUGAAAGAGUAGACACUACUACCAACCUUACAGAAAUGGGCAAUCUGAAUAGACCUAUAACUAGUGAACAGAUUAAACCAGGAAUCAGAAAAUUGCCCACAAAGAAUAGUCCAGGCACAGACAGUUUUACCACUGUGUUCUACCAAACAAUCAAAUAAAUUAUAGCAAUUAUUCUCAAACUCUUUCAAGAAAUAGGAGGGAGUACUUCCCAGUAUUGCCCUGAUAACAAAACUGCUCAAAGAUAUUACAAGAAAACUGCAGACCAAUAUGUCUUAUGAAAUACCUGCAAAAAUCCUCAACUAAAUGCUGCAAACCAAAUCCAGCAACAUAUAAAAAUAAUUAUGCACCAUCACCAAGUAGGAUUUAUCCCAGGGAUAUAAGAUUGGCUUAACAUGUGAAAAUCAAUGUAAUACAUUAUAUCAAUAUAAUAAAAAAGUCAUCUCUACUGAUGCAAAAAUAGCUGCAUUUGAAUAAAUCCAACACCCUUUCAUCAUAAAAAUGUUUGAAAAACGAGGAACGGAAGGAAACUACCUUAACCUGAUAAAGAACAUCUAUGAAAAAUCUACAGCUUUCUUUAUACUUAAUGGUGAAAAACUGAAUGCUUUCCCACUGAGAUUAGAAAUAAGACAAGGAUGCCCAUUAUCACACUUCUAUUUAACAUUGUACUGGAGGGUCUAAGCCAUUGCAAUUAUGCAAGAAGAAAAUAAAGGUUGGAAAGGAAGAAGAAAGACUGUUCACAAAUGACAUGAUCUUGUAUGUAGAAGAUUCUAGGGAAUCCACCAAAAAAAAAAAAAAAAACUAUUGAAACUAAUAAGUGAGUUCAGCAAGAUGGGAGGAUACAACAUCAGUAUUUAAAAAUCAGUUGGGCCGGGCAUGGUGGCUCACGCCUGUAAUCCCAGCACUUUGGGAGGCCGAGGCAGGUGGAUCAUGAGGUCAGGAGAUCAAGACCAUCCUGGCUAACACGGUGAAACCCUGUCUCCACUAAAAAUACAAAAAAUUAGCCAGGCGUGGUGGCGGGUGCCUGUAGUCCCAGCUACUUGGGAGGCUGAGGCAGGAGAAUGGCAUGAACCUGGGAGGCGGAGCUUGCAGUGAGCCAAGAUUGUGCCACCGCACUCCAGCCUGGGUGACAAAGCGAGACUCCAUCUCAAAAAAAAAAAAAUCGUAUUUCUACACACUUGCAAUGAAUAAUCAAAAAUGAAAUUAAGAAUAUUCAUAAUAGCAUCAAAAAGAAUAAGGUGCUUAAUAACAUAUUUAACAAAAAGUGCAAAACUUACACUCUGAAAACUACAAAACAUUGCAGAAAGUAAUUAAAGAAGACCUAAAUAAAUGGAAAAACAUGCCAUGUUCAUGGAUCAGAAGAGUUAAUGCUGUUAAGAUGACAAUAUUCCUCAAACUUGUCUGCAGAUUCAGCAUAAUCCCUGUCAGAAUCUCUGCUGACAUCUUUGCAGAAAUUGACAAGCUGAUGCUAAGAGUUAUAUGAAAUUUCAAGGGACCCAGAAUAGCCAAAGAAAUCCUGAAAAAGAAUAAAGUAGAAAAACCCACAUUUCUUCAUUUUGAAUUACAAAACAAUAGUAAUUAAGAAGUGUGUUACUGGCACAAGGGUAGACAUAGAUCAUUGUAUUUUUUUAAAAAAUGGUGAUUCCAGAAAUAAAUGCAAACAUCUGUAGUCAACUGAUUUUCAGUAAAGGUGCCAAGUCCAUUCAGUGGGGAAAGAACAGUCUUUUCAACAAAUGGUGCUGGGACAAGUGGAUAGUCACGUGCAAAAGAAUGAAGUUGGACACUUACCUUACAUUAUAUUUAAAAAGUUGGCUGGGUAUGACGGCCCAUGCCUGUAGUCUUAGCACUUUGGGAGGCAAAGGGGCAGAUUGCUUGAGUCCAGGAGUUUCAGACCAGCCUGGGCAACAUGGCAAAGUCAUGUCUCUACAGAAAAAACAAGUUAGCUGGUCAUGGUCAUGUGCAUCUGUAGUCCCAGCUACUCAGGAGGCUAUGGUGAGAGGAUCACUUGAGCCCAGGAGGUCAAGGUUGUAGUGAUCCAUGAGCAUGCCACUGUACUCCAGCCUGGGUGACAGAGCAAGACCCUAUCUCAAAAAAAAGAAAAAAGAAAACAAGUUAAAAUAGAUGAAAGAGGCCAGGCGCGGUGGCUCACGCCUGUAAUCCUAACACUUUGGGAGGCUGAGGUGGGCAGAUCAUAAGGUCAGGAGUUUGAGAGCAGCCUGGUCAAUAUGGUGAAACCCUGUCUCUACUAAAAAUACAAAAAUUAGCUGGGCGUGGUGGCGUGCACCUGUAGUCCCAGCUACUUGGGAGGCUGAGGCAGAAGGAUCACUUGAACCCAGGAGCCGAGAUUGUGCCACUGCGUUCCAGCCUGGGUGACAGAGUGAGACUCUGUCUCAAAAAAAAAAAAAAAAAAAAAAAAAAGACCUAACUAUCAAAGCAAAACCUAUAAAACUCUUAGAAGAAAAUGGGUAAAUCUUCAUGAACUUGGGCUUGGCAAGCAUUCUAAGAUAUGACAUUAAAAACACAAGCAGCAAAAGAAGAGAAUUUGGACUUCAUUGAAAUUUAAAGCUUUUGUGCUUUGAAGGAUACCAUCAAGAAAGGGAAAAGACAACCUACAGAAUUGGAGAAAAUAUUUGUGAAUCAUAUCUAAUAAAGACUCAGAAAUAACUUUAAAAAUGGACAAAGGAUCUGAUUAGACAUUUUCCCAAAUAUAUAAAAAUGGCCAAUAAGCACAUGAAAAGAUGCUUGACAUCAUUAGUCAUCAGGGAAAUGCAAAGCAAAACCACAAUGAGAUAUCACUUCACACCCACUAAGUUGGCUAAAAUAAAAAAGAUAGUAACAAGUGUUGACAAGAGAUUGUAGAGAGAUUGGAAGCCACAGAUACUGCUGGUGAGAAUGUAAAAUGGUGCAGCCACUUUAGAAAACAGUUGCAAUUUCUCAAAUGAUUAAACACAGAGCUAGCCUAUGACCUAGAAAUUCCUCUCCUAGGUAUAUAACCAAGUGAAAUGAAGACUUAUGUCCACACAGAAACUUGUAAAUGAAUCUCUAGCAGCAUUGUUCGUAAUAGCCAAAAAGUGGAAACAGCUCAAAUAUACAUCAAUAGGUGAAUGGAUUUUAAAAUGCAGUAUAUCUAUACAAUGGAAUAUUAUUCAGCCCCAAAAAGCAAUGAAGGACGGAUACACUGAUACAUGCUAUAACACUGAUGAACCUCUAAAAUUUCCUGCUAAGUGAAAAAGUCAUGAAAGACCACAUGCUAUGAUCCCAUCCAUAUAAAAGUCCAGAAUAGGGAAAUCUAUAGAAACAGGAAGUAGGUUAGUGGUUGCUUAAAGAAAGAGUGGUAAGUAGGUUGCUUAAAGGGUCAUAAGUGGGGACAAUAGUUAAAAAGUUGGGGGUUUGGAGGUGAUUUUUAGGUUUUCAGAUGAUGAAAAUGUAAAAUUGAGGUGGUGAUGGUUGCAUGUAUCUUUGAGUAUACUAAAAGCUACUGAAUUGUACUACUGAAAUAAAUGAGUUAUAUGGUAUAUGAAUUAUAUCUCAGUACAGUUGUUAAUAAAUAAUUAACAUAAGGUGCAAGAUAAAUUGGGAGCUUAACAAAAAGACAACCCAAUUAAAAAUGCUUGAAGAAUCUGAAUAGACAUUUCCCAAAGAAGAUAUACAAAUGGCCAAAAAGCACAUGAAAAGAUGCUUGACAUCAUUAGUCUUUAGGGAAAGGCAAGUCAAAACUGUGAUGAGGUACCACUUCACAGUCACUAGCAUGACUAUAAUAAUUUUUUUAAAACUCAAUAACAAAUGUUGACAAGGACAUGGAUAAGCAAACCUUUAUACAUUGCUGGUGAGAAUGUAAAAUGGUGCAACCACUGUGAAAAAUAGUUUGGUGUUUCCUCAAAAAGUUAAACAUACAAUUACCAUAUGAUCCAACAAUUAUACUUUGUGGAAUAUUCCACAAACUGAAAACUGGUGCUCAAACAAAUACUUGUAUGUGAAUAUUCAUAGUAGCACUAUUCACAAUGGUCAAAAUGUGGACACAGUUGAAGCGUCCAUUGACAGAUGAAUAGAUAAACAAAAUGUGGUCUAUCUACACAGUGGAAUAUUACUCAGCCACAAAAGGGAUGAAGUACUGAUGCAACAAGGAUGACACAGAAGAUAACAUAUAUUGUAUGAUACCAUUUAUAUAAAAUACACAGAACAGGGAAUUCUAUAGACAGAAAGCAGAUGAAUGGUUGUGAGAGGCUGGGGUGGGGAGGGGGAUGGGGAGUGAUUUCUUUCUUUCUUUUUUUUUUUUUGAGACAGUCUUGCUCUGCUGCCCAGGCUGGAGUGCAGUGGCACGAUCUUGGCUCACUGCAAGCUCCACCUCCCAGGUUCACGCCAUUCUCCUGCCUCGGCCUCCUGCCUCAGCCUCCCAAGUAGCUGGGACUACAGGUGCCCGCCACUAUGCCCGGCUAAUUUUUUUUGUAUUUUUUUAGUAGAGAUGGGGUUUCACCAUAUUAACCAGGAUGGUCUCGAUCUCCUGACCUUGUGAUCUGCCCGCCUCGGCCUCCCAAAGUGCUGGGAUUACAGGCGUGAGCCACCACGCCCAGCUGGGGAGUGAUUUCUUAAUGGGUAUAGGGUUCUUUUAUGGGGUGAUGAAAGUGCUUUGGAACCAGAUGGAAGUGGUGAUCGCACAACAUUGUGAAUGUACUAAAGGCUGCUGAUUUGUACACUUUAAAAAAUAUCUUCAGGUGUUCAAUAUUGCUUUCAGUCUAUUUUGGUAAGAUUUUUCUAGAAAAUUGUUUAUUUUGUCUGUUUUAAAAGUUGUUCCUUUGUGGAUAUCAUCUGUUUGUCAUUGGUGUUCUGCAGUUUCAUUAUGAUUUAUGUGUCUUUUUUCCACAUAAAUUUUUCAAAGUUAUUCCUUUGUGGUUAUCAUCUGUUUGUCAUUGGUGUUCUGCAGUUUCACUCUGAUUUAUGGGUGUUUUUCCCCUUCUGGUUCAGUCCUCAGAGAUAUGUGGAUUUAUUUUUAUCCUGUAUGGAGCCUGUGCUUCCUGAAUUUAAGGAUUCAUGUCCUUCAACAGUUCUGGAAGACUGUAGCCAUUAUUUCUUUGAAUACUGCCUCUCCUCAUUUGCUUUCACCCUUCUGGAACUUUUUAUUUCUAACUUUCUGGUUAAGCUAUCCAUUGAAUUUUUAUUAUUAUUUUUUGAGACAUAGUUUCACUUUUGCCCAGGUUGAAGUGCAGUGGCACGAUCAUAGCUCAGAUCAUAGCUCACUGCAAACUUUUGACCAUAGCUCACUGCAACCUCGAACUCUUGGGCUCAAGUGAUCCUCCCGCCUCAGCCUCCCAAGAGGCUGGGGCUACAGGCAGAUGCCACCACACCUGGCUGAAGUUUGAAAAUUUUUUCAGAGAGACAGAGUCUCGCUGUGUCACCCAGGCCAGUCUUGAACUCUUGGCUCAAGUGAUCCUCCUGCUUUGGCCUCCCAAAGCACUGGGAUUACAUGUAUGAGGCACUGUGCCCAGCCUGAAUUUUUAAUUUUAUAAUCAUAAUGUUUAUUUCUAAAAUUGUUUCUUCCUCCCCUCUAAGCUUCCCAAUUUUGUCUUACAAUGCUUUUUUCUUAUUUUUUCUUCUUGUGGCUAUAAUAAUUUUAAACACCACUGUUUCAUAGACUCCAUCAGAUUACUGCACUGGCUGGAGGUCUUGCUGUUGAUCCUGCUCUUUGUGGUGUCUGCUGGCUCUCCCUCACAGUAAAUUGGGGGGUGUGUGUGUGUGUGUGUGUGUGUGUGUGUGACGUUUUUGUGUGUAAAGAUGGGUGAGUCAUCUUCAAAGGGGCUUUCUCACCAGCAUGGUUUUUGUAUGUGCUUGCAUCUGAUGGUUAUUAUCAGCCUGGGACCAAUUUUUUCUGUUAAUUUCUUAACUUUCAAUAUUUUGGAUCUUGUGGUAAUGUAAGUUUGGACUUCAAACUCAUGUGAACUUAUAGUUAUGAAUUGUCUGAGUGUAGAGGUGGGGUGAGAUAUGAGGGAGGAUAAGUCCCCCACUAAGAAUCCAGCUCAAACAGCAAAGCUUCUCUGUAGCGGGAGGUAGAUUCUAUUAAUAUUCUAGCCCACUGUUUUUCUGAGGCCAUACCUGUAUGAGGGGGUCUCAGUUCUGAUUCUUUUUCUAAAGCAAGCCCAUAUUUUUGUCUGCUACCCAUGCCUUGGUGUUAAAUCCAAACUUCUGUAUUUCAGGAACAGCACUUUUCAGGGAAUAUGGACCACUCUAUUUAUAGUUUCUUUCUCGUUUGUAGCCCCUGGCACUUGACUUUGCUAAGAUCUCAGCUAUGUCGUUAAACGGAUUUUUGUCACAUUAUAUUUAACAUUAUAAAUAACAUUUCUUGUUUAGAAGGCCUUUUGGGUAAUCUUAUCUGUUACAUUGCUGAAACCAUUACAUUUUUUAAUUUGUCAUGUUGGUCUAAAGAGCUUAGAAUAGUGCCUGGCACAAAAAUAAGAGCUGUGUGUGUUAGCAGUUUCAUUUUUAUGUUACUUUUCUUAUUUUUAUUACUGCUGGAUUAUCUUUAUAGUUCUAAAGCUUCAGCAACUGGUUCUCAUAUUUUCUAGAUAUACCAAAGAUCAUCUACAAAUAACGACAUGAUUGCCUCUUUCUUUUCAGUAUUUAUAAACCUUAUUCUUUUCUUACUGUGCUACCAUCUUCCUCUAGCCCCGCAUUUGCCAGGAAUGGUGAUGGGAGUGGUCAUCUGUGUCUUUUUCCUAACUUAAAUGAGGAAUGCUUUGCAUGUGUGAAGCAUAUGUGCUCUAAAUUUCUGGUUGACACCUUUUAAUGAGUUAAGAACCCUUUUCCUGUUCCUAGCUUACAAAUAGUUUUCAUUAGAAACAAAUUAUGAAUUUUUUAGUUGCAUUUUCUACAUUUACUGAAAUGACAAUACUUCUUUAAUCUACUAGGUUUCUGAAUUGGAUUAGUAUAGUAUAUUUAGUGUUUUUUUGUUGUUGUUUUUUUUAAAUCAACUCAUCAUUCCUAGAAUAUUCCUAAUCCUGGGAUGAAGGUGGGGAACCCCUAUUUGGUCAUGAUAUAUUUCGCUUUUAAUAUACUGCUGGUUUCAAUUGGCUAAUACUUUAUUAGAUUUUUAACCUCUCAGAUCAUAAGGGAAAUUGCUGUAUAGUUAUUUUUUCUUUACUUUUUGCUGUGCUGUGUGUGUGUGCAUGCAUGCAUGUGUGAAAGUUGUUCUUGUCUUGGAAAAUAAAUUGGGAAAUACUCCACCUUUUUAUGUUCUCAGAAGAGUUCCUGUAACAUAGGAAUUACAUGCACAUUUCAUAGACUACUUGUAAAACUGGGCUUUUGUACAUUUUGGAAGAAUGUUUCAGCUCAAUCCUCGUACUCACUCAAUUGCUUUUCAAUAGUGUCCAUUCUGAUAUUCUGCCCAUGCCCCGAUGUUUUUCUUUUAAUUUCACAAUCGACUGUUCUCUCCUAGGAUUUGCCCUUGGUCCUUCUUUCGUAAUGCUCUGUCCUGUGUCAUGGAUGCACUGGGCUCUCCUAAAAUAUAGGAUAUAUCCUCCCCAUCUCCUUUUGCCUCCUCCAGUGCUGCAGUUGGUUGAGUUUUGUGGUGUUGGUUUUCUUCAGAUCUUGGGUGGUCUUAGCUAUGUUUGAUAUAUUUGAGACCCCCUGUUUGCCUGUCCUGUUGAUCCUGUGGAUCCUACACUGCCUCCAGCGCUGUGGAGAGAGCUGGGUUGGGCUGCUGAGGAGGGUGUCCAGGAGCGAGUCUCAGUAGGGUGAAGGCUCCCAUUUCUCCUGGUGAAUUCCAGCCCUGAGGGCAUGGCAAGGCCUCUUUGUCGAAGUGUCCACAGAAAUGUCUGGGGCAGGGGUAGACAAAGGUCUCUGCAUGGCAAGGGCAGGGGAAGGAGGACCUAAUCCUUGGCUGAUCCUAAUGCAGUGACCCUGUGGGCCCAGCACACCUCUCCUUGCCAGCACUCCCACCUUGGCAGCCGCCACCUGCCCCAUCUGAGUAUGCUUUCCUUCUUAUCCUAUGUGGUUUUUGAUUCACAGUGGCCUUCCUUUUCCUGUCGUCAACCACUUAUGAAUGUAUAUACAGACAGGUGUCACUUAAUGACAGGGAUAUGAGGACACGUUCUGAGCAGCAUGUCAUAGGCACUUUUAUCAUUGUGCUAGCCUCAUAGAGUGACUUAUCCAAACCUCAGUGGUACAGCUACUACACACCUAGGCUAUAUGGCUACAAACCUGUACAGCAUGUGACUGUACUGAUUGCUGUAGGCAGUUGUAACAUAAUGGUAUUUGUGUAUCUGAACAUAUCUAAACACAGAAAAGGUGCAGAAAAAAUAUGGUAUAAAAGAUAGCAAAUGGUACACCCCUAUAGGACACUUCUGACUGGAGCUUGGAGGACUGGAAGUUGCUCUGGGUUUGUCAGUGAGUGUAAGUGAAUGUGAAGGCCUAAGACAUUACUGUACACUUUUAUACAACUGGCAGUGCAGUAGGGUUGUUUACAACAGCAUCAAGAUAAACACAUAAUAUAUUGCACUGCAAUGUUCUGAGGGCUGUGAUGUACUAGGUGGUAAGAAUUUUUUAGCUCUAUUAUAGUCUUUUGGGACCACCAUUGUGUAUUCCAUCCAUGAUUGACUGAAACAUCAUUAUGUGGUGUAUGAUUGUAUAUAUCUAAAUAGUAUACAAGUAUUUAUGAGUUUUUUUGCGUGUACUUUUUUUUCUGUUGUCUUGGAAUUUUGUCUUCAUCUAAUGACAUUGAUUUAACUUCCUUUAACCUCAGUUUAUAAACACUUAAUUUAUGAAAGUAAUUGUAGAACAUAUUUUUAAAAUCUGAAUCUUUACAACACAAAUGGCAAAAGGUUCUUUCAGAAGUUAGAAUUCAGUUUCCCAUUCAAUGUCUGUUCUGUUAAAUCACUGGGAACGUCAUUUACGCAAAGGCAGAAGAAGAGGUAACUUCCUGCCCACCAAGCCACACUAACGGUACAUUUUACACCCUCAUUGGCACAAGCGUCAGAAGUAAAUGAAAACAAAAUCACUCUAUCUGCAGACAGAGUGACACUCUAACAUUUUCAGUCUGUUGGGUAUGUUUUAAUCCUAAAAUUAAUGUUUGGAAUAGAAUUUUGAAAUUGUUUUAAUCUGGAGAAUAAAAAUUACAUUUUGCUGAGCAAGUAAACUGAACUUAAAAUAGAAAAUAUUUUUCACUAAAAAUAGGAAUAAAAAGAUGGAAGUGAAGAAUGGAAAGAAGUCUGCAGUGAGCAGCUUGAGAAGGUAAUUGUUCAUCUGAACAAAAGAAAUUCUUGUAGUCCUAUGGCCUUCCUGGUUCCAUGGCCACCUGCCCCCAGCAUGGUCAACCAAGCACAGUGUGAUGUGCUGACAAUCUCACCUUGUGUGCAUUGUGGGUUUCAGAUUUGGAAAAAGACUGGCAUCAGCUUCCACGGAGAUUACUGUAUUGUUUUGUGCAGUUUCUGAAUUUAAGACAGGAAAAAUCUGACUAAUGCAUAUCACCAGCAUCGUGGCUGUCAAGAAUUUCUAUGUUGUUUCAACUUUCUGCUUCUUUGGGAGAGAGGAAGGGCAGCACCUUAGCUUUGUGCCUUGGUUUGAGGAACCGUGUUUCUCAAUAUUGGCCACCACCAUUGAUCCUUUUCUUCUUCACAGGGAAUUCGGUGCCCUGUGCCUUUGCUUUCGCUUUGCAAGACAAUCAAGGCCGACCUGGGCAUGGGUCCCCACUCAGCGUCCCGACCCCGCACCGGGCGCUGAGGCAGAGAGCGCGAGAGGGCGGGGGUCCACCUUCUUCCUCAGUGGCAGCUCACCCGUGCGUAACUGUCGUUUGGAGGACAGUGAUACAAGUUAGGAAAACCAGGCAUUUGUUUAACUCUUCUGCCUGAGGAAAAGCAAUGUUGGACAUUUGCAGUUCUGGCGAUUCAGCUUGGUUUUCCUAAAAGACAGGCCCCCACCCCUUCCCCCGGGGGCGCGGGUCUUGUUUGGAUACCGGCAGCCUGGGGCCAGGGAUGUGCUAGGGCAACAAAGAUGGUCCUGGAGGAGGAGGCCGUUCGUUUCUGCCGCUCCCGGGAGUUUUUGGGCUCAACUCACAGGACGAAGUUUUGCUUUCAGUGGUAAAGCACACUUUCUCCCGCCUGCUUUUGUUCCUGUCUGGUUCUUGCAUAUGCUGCCUUUUCUCCUUUUAGUUUUUAGUUGGUCGUAAACAGUAAUAUAAAUAAACAAACCAAAACAAAGCGCGGUGUAACUACCUGUGACACCAGGAAAACCCUGUGCACAGCGGGGCUGGCGCUGCGGGCGGACAGCGUUGGGCCCACCCGAGCUCCCUGGCUGCGAACUCUCUGCUCCCGUCCGCACCCGCUGCCACCCACAGACAGGAAAUACAGCACCCCACCUGCGGAGACGCCGGCGGCUGGGGGACAGCACGCUUUGUUAAGAAAUCAGAAUGCAAAAUGGCACACCGUGCACAACUGGGUCUACACAGGCAAGGGAAGAGGAGGAAAUGUAAACAGCUGUCCCGAGUUUACUAAGAGGGCAAAGUGAGUAAAUUUUUUUCAUUAGUCCUGCUUUCACAACAAUCGCAUUUUAGAAUAACUGUAACUUGUAUUGAGAGGGAGGCCCCUCCUCCACUUCGUGACCACAGUGUGGAAGCUGCACUGCGGGCAGCCAGGGUUUUCCUCGGCCUCCAUAGAAAGACGCUUAACUUCUUAUAUGGUUGUGGCAAGCACUAAAAUCCUGAUUUUUACAGAAUAGUAGUAAAAAUGCCUCAGUGACUUACUUUGAAAACAGUACAUUGGUACAUGGCUCUUGUACCCAGUAUCAGGAAUGUACAAAUGUCUUUUUAUUCAAAAGUACAAAAUGAAUUAUCUGUAGGCACGGACAAUGACAGCAAUAAACCAUUAUAUAUUUUGUCAACUGAAACCAGUAACUGAUGGUUAUAGUGAUUUCUUAAACAUCAGCCAGCCUUUUCUUCAUUUUCUCCAACUGACUUCUCUGAAAUUAUUAGUGAGGAACACUGCCUUGGGCUUCCUGUCACAGCUCAUUAAUAAAGGUAAAGCACUAUUCUAGGAAUUAGAACAUGCCACCUCUCAUACCACCUCCCAUUCCACCCAUUCCAGGGUUCUUCUCUUCUUUAGGAAUUUCUGUGACUACAGCUUCUGCUGUAGUUAACAGAGAGGCCAUGCCAUCAGCAUCCAAUAUAGUAGUGCCCACCAUGCCUGCCCCAUUCCUGUAACCCCCGCCUGGCUGCUCACCAGUUUCCUCUCAGAGAUUUCCUCUCCCUAUUUUUGAGUUAAUUAUUGACUUCUUUUUGAAACCUCCCUUUUAGACUUGUGCAUUUUUGAAGGCAGAAUUAAAUGGUGCCAUUCUGCCUUUUGCAAUGAUGACCUUGCAUCUUUGGUUUAACAGUUACCAAGAUAUUAAGCAAAAUUUGUCUCAGAUCUUUUCUUUUUCCCUUAAAGACAUACAUGUGACAAAAAGAAUUAGCCACCCCAGUUCCUUUUCAUGUCCUCUCUCUGCAGAGGUAACUCUCUGAUGUGGUGUGGCUGUGCCCCCACCCAAAUCUCAACUUGAAUUGUAGAUCCCAGAAUUUCCAUGUGUUGUGGGAGGGACCAGGCGGAGGUAAUUGAAUCAUGAGGGCCGGUCUUUCCCAUGCUAUUCUCAUGGUAGUGAACAAGUCUCACGAGAUCUGAUGGGUUUAUCAGGGGUUUCUGCUUUUGCUUCUUUCUCAUUUUCUUUUGCCAUCACCAUGUAAGAAGUGCCUUUCACCUCCUGCCAUGAUUCUGAGGCCUGCCCAGCCAUGUGGAACUGUAAGUCCAAUUAAACCUCUUUUUCUUCCCAGUCUUGCGUAUGUCUUUAUUAGCAGCAUGAAAAUGGACUAAUACAGUCAGUUGGUACCAGUAGAAUGGAAUGUUGCUGAAAAGAUACCCAAAAAUGUGGAAGUGACUUUGGAACUGGGUAAUAGGCAGAGGUUAGAACAGUUUGGAAGGCUCAGAAGAGGACAGGAAAAUGUGGGAAAGUUUGGAACUCCCUGGAGACUUGUUGAAUGGGUUUGACCAGAAGCCUGAUAGCAAUAUGGACAAUAAGGUCCAGACUGAGGUGGUCUCAGAUGGAGAUGAGAAACUUGUUUUGGGAACUGGAGUGAAGGUGACUCUUGUUACGUUUUAGCAAAGAUACUGGCAGCAUUUUGCCCCUGCCCUAGAGAUGUGUGGGACUUUGAACUUGAGAGCAAUGAUUUAGGGUAUCUAGCGGAAGAAAUUUCCAAGCAGCAAAGCAUCCAAGAGAUGACUUGGAGGCUGUUAAAGGCAUUUAGUUUUAUAAGGGAAGCAGUGCAUAAAAGUUUGGAAAAUUUGCAGCCUGACAAUGUGAUAGAAAAGAAAAACCCAUUUUCUGAGGAGAAAUUCAAGUCGGCUGUAGAAAUUUGCAUAAAGUAACGAGGAGCCAAAUGUCAGUCCCCAAGAGGAUGGGGGAAAAUGUCUCCAGGACAUGUCAGAGGUCUUCACAGCAGCUCCUCCUAUCACAGGCCCGAAGGCCUAGGAGGAAAAAAGUGGUUUCAUGGGCUGGGCCCAGGGUCCCCCAGCUGUGUGCAGCCUACGGACUUGGUGUCCUGCAUCCCAGCUGCUCCAGCUGUGGCUGAAAGGGGCCAACAUAGAGCUCAGGCCAUGGCUUCAGAUGGUGCAAGCCCCAAGCCUUGGCAGCUUCCACAUGGUGUUGAGCCUGAGGAUGCACAGAAGACAAGAAUUGAGGUUUGGGAACCUCCACCUGGAUUUCAGAAGAUGUAUGGAAAUGCCUAGAUGCCCAGGCAGAAGUUUGCUGCAGGGGCGGGGCACUCAUGGAGAACCUUUGCUAGGGCAGUGUGGAAGGAAAUGUGGAGUCAGGGCCCCCAGGCAGAGUCCCUACUGGGGCAUCACUUAGUGGAGCUAUAAGAAGAGGGCCACUGUCCUCCAGACCCCAGAAUGGUAGAUGCACCAACAGUUUGCACUGUGCACCUGGAAAAGCCGCAGACAAUGGCAGCCCAUGAAAGCAGCUGGGCAGGAGUCUGUACCCUGCAAAGCCACAGGGGCGGAGCUUCCCAAGACCAUGGGAACCUACUUUUUACAUCAGCGUGACCUAGAUGUGAGACUUGGAGUCAAAGGAGAUCGUUUUGGAGCUUUAAAAUUUGACUGCCCUGCUGGAUUUUGGAUGCAUGGGUCCUGAAACCCUUUUGUUUUGGCCAAUUUCUCCCAUUUGGAACGGCUGUAUUUACCCAAUACCUGUACCUCCAUUCUAUGUAGGAAGUAACUAGCUUGCUUUUGAUUUUACAGGCUCAUAGGCAGAAGGGACUUUCCUUGUCUUGGAUGAGACUUUGGACUGUUGACUUUUGGGUUCAUACUGAAAUGAGUUAACACUUUGGGGGACUGUUGGGAAGGCAUGAUUGGUUUUCAAAUGUGAGGACAUGAGAUUUGGAGGGGUUGGGGCAGAAUGAUAUGGUUUGGCUGUGUCCCCUCCCAAAUGUUGCAUUGUAGCUCCCAGAAUUCCCAUGUGCUGUGGGAGGGACCCAGUGGGAAGUAAUUGAAUCAUGGGGGCUGGUCUUUCCCAUGCUAUUCUUGUGAUAGUGAAUAAAUUUCACGAGAUCUGAUGGGUUUAUCAGGGGUUUCCACUUUUUCUACUUUCUCACUUUCUCUUGCCACUGCCAUGUAAGAAGUGCCUUUUGCCUCCCACCAUGAUUCUGAGGCCUCCCCAGCCAUGUAGAACUGUAAGUCCAGUUAAAUCUCUUUUUCUUUCCAGUCUCUGGUUGUCUUUAUCAGCAGGUUGAAAAUGGACUAAUAUACUCCCCUUCUAAAGUUGACGUGUAUUGGUCUCCAGGCAUGCUUCAUUCACUGACCAUGCCUUCCUGGCCAUCGCUGUCCCUGGGGUCCACACUGGAUCUGCAGUGUGGUUGGAUCUGCAGUGUGGUUGGAUCUGCAACCAACUGCAGUUCAAGAAUACGUUUUUAGAAAAUAACAAUACAAUAAAAUAUAAUACAAACAAAAAACAAUACAGUAUGACAACUAUUUGCCUAGCAUUUACAUUGUAUUAGGUAUUGCAAGUAGUCCAUAAAUGGUGUAAAGUACACAGGAGGAUGUGCCUAUGUUAUAUGCACAUGUGUCCUAUUCUCAAAUGGUUAUUUAAAUUUUGACUUUAACUGUAAUUACUUUUUUAAAAUAUUUUUAAGACUAUUUCCAUGUUUUUCUUCCCUUUAUUCACCUUGAUCUCAUGCUGGAGGUUUGUCUCUCUUAUUAGUCUCUUCAAAAAAUCAGCCUUUUAUUAUUUAUUUGAUUACUCUGUUGUUAACUUUCUAACAGACCUCAGGUGCUCAGAACCAGAUAAGCCAGAAUUCUUGGCAGAAGAGGCUCCCUGUCAUCCUGUCAUGCCUGUUUUAUUUUGGUUAUGCCUGUACUAGUAAGCACCCAUGAACCCACUCUCCAGAAUUAGAGAAAGGACACCCCAAUAACUCACAGCUACCUGUCUAUUCCUCUCCUCUCCUCCACCUUUCUUCCCCAGCUAGUAAACACUAUUCUCAGUUUUGUACUAUUUCCUUGCUUAUAUGUUUGUAUAUACCUAGAAGAACAUUAUUUUUAGUUGUUCUUAAUGUAAUAAAAAGGGAUCUUGCUGUACUUAAUAUUCUGAGACUUUGUUUUUAAAGUCAAUGUUAUACUGGUGUGUUUUAUCCACAUUAUUGCAUGUAGCUGUAUAUAUUAGUCCGUUUUCAUGCUGCUGAUAAAGACAUACCUGAGACUGGGUAAUUUAUAAAGAAAAAGAAGUUUAAUGGACUCACAGUUCCACAUGGCUGGGGAGGCUUCAUAAUCAUGGCGGAAGGCAAGGGAAGAACAAAGAUAUGUCUUAUAUGGCAGCAGGUGAGAGAGAAUGAGAACCAAGCAAAAGGCAUUUCCCCUUAUAAAACCAUCGGAUCUCCUGAGACUUAUUCACUACCACAAGAACAGCAUGGGGGAAACCACCCCCCAUGAUUCAAUCAUCUCUCACCGGGUGCUUCCCACAACAGGUGGGAAUUAUGGGAGCUACAAUUCAAGAUGAAAUUUGGUGGGGACACAGCCAAACCAUAUCACUGUACUUUUAAGUUUCACCAUGGUAUGAUAUGCCAUUUUGUAAAUAUUCCACAAUUUAUCUAUUCUCUCUUACCUGGUUCUAAUUUCUUAUUACCUAUGUGAUUUCUUAUUGAAAGGCAUUCAGUUAUCUCAGGUUUUUCCAUUAUAAAUACUGCAGCUAUUAACACUUUGAUAUAUGCCUCCCGGUACACAUGAGUGAGGUUGUCUCUUGGACAUAGAGCCAGGAAUGGAAUUGUAUCCAUUGUGCCAACUAUUACACUUUAAGUAUAAGAAAUCCUGCUGAUUUGUAUCCUUUCCAAUAUGUAAUGCUAUCAGACUUUAAUUUUUGUAGACCAAAUUAGUUUAAAAUCUCAUUCUGACCUUUAUUUGAUUUUCUUUAUGUCUAAUGGUUUCAGACAUUUCUUCAUGUGUGUUUCCUUUUCAGUUCUUUUUCCUGUUCAUUUUUAUUGGCUUGUUUGUCCUUCUCUUAUUGAUUUGUAGGGGUUCUUUGUAUUCUUGAUUCAGAUUCAGUGUAGAUUAUGUAAAUAUUAUCUCCAAGUUUCUAAUGUGUCUUUCUGUUUCACUAAGUUAUUUGUUGAUGAGCUUACUUUUUUAUAUAUAGUCAAAUUUAUCAAUCUUUUAUUUUAUUGCUAGUGUUUGCUGUGUCUUUUUUAAAAAAUCUUUUCCUACUCUACAUUUGGAAAGACUUUUACUUAUAUUUCCUAGUGAAAUUUUUACUUUUGUCAUUUAAGUACUUAAUCCAGCUAGAAUUAAUUUUUAAGCAUGGAGAGAGGUAGAGGUUCAAUUUCAUUUGUUUCCCCAAAUGAAUAUGCUCAUCAUCAUUUUCUUCCUUUGGUGGCUUUGGAAUUUAGUCUGUUAAUUCUUCAAAUAAUAAUUUGAGUUAGAUCCUUGUUUCAUAGUUUUUUAGUCUUCCUUGCUUUUUUUUUUUUUCUUUCUUUCUUUUUUUUGAGACAGUCUGAUUCUGUCGCCCAGGCUGGAGUACAGUGGCACGAUCUCGGCUCACUGCAACCUCCUCCGGCUCCCAGGUUCAAGUGAUUCUCCUGCUUCAGCCUCCUGAGUAGCUGGGAUGACAGGCGCCUGCCACCAUGCCCAGCUAAUUUUUGUAUUUUUAGUAGAGACGAGGUUUCACCAUGUUGGCCAGGCUGGUCUUGAACUCCUGACCUCAAGUGAUCCACCCGCCUCAGCCUCCCAAAGUGCUGAGAUUACAGGUGUGAGCCAUUGCACCCUGCCCUCUUCCUUGCUUUUUAAUACUUGCAUUUAAAGCUAUAACUUUCCCUCUAAGUACUGCUUUAGGUUCAUCCUAUAUUUUUUAUAUGCUAUGCAUUCAUCAUUAUUUGAUUCUAAUUUCUAAUUUUCAAUAUGAUUUCUUCCAAUUCAUAAGCUAUUUAAAGUGUUGAAUUUUCAAAUACAUUUGCAGGGUUGACUGUCUUUCUGUAAUUGAUUUUUAGUGCUGUUUCACUGUGGUCAGAGACUGUGCUCUGCGUGGGAUUGGCUAUUUUGGUGUUUCUUGAGGCCACUUUUGUUGCUUAGCAACUGAUCAGAAUGUGCUGAUUGUUGGGUGUUCUGUGACUGUUUAUUAGGUCAAGUAUGUAAACUGGGUUGCUUAAAUUUUCUGUGUCCUUGCUAAUCUUUAUUUUCCCUGCUUAAUCUAUCAAUUACUGAACGAAGGUAUGUGAACUUUUCCAUUAUUAUAUGGAUUUUAAAAUUUCUCUUUAUAAAUCUAUCAGUUUUUGAUUUUUCUGUUUUAAGACUAUAUUGUUAGAAACAUACAGAUUCUGGAUUUUAAAAAUAUCUUUAUGGUGAAUUUUCAUUGUCAUAUAUGAUAGAAAUUGUUCCCAUGAUCACAUGAUAACCUCUUUCACCCUAAUAAUGCUUUUUGUCUUGUUUAUUUUGUCUAAUGUAAGUAUAGCUAGAACUGUUCUCUUUUGAUUAAUAUUUGCCUAGUAUGUUUUUUCAUUUAUCAUUUUACAAAUAAUUUUCAUCAGUAUACAGAUAAUUUUCAUCAGUAUACAAACAUAGUCAAUGUAUAACUGAGAUUACUAAUAAAUUUGGAUUUAUUUCUGUCA